UCUCGCCUGCUCCCCUUUCCCUCCCGGGGACCAAGACCCGCCCCCUUCCCUUCUCUCUCCCAGCCCCAUCUCACUCCUUCCUCCCCGCGAGACCCUGCCUCGGCCCUAGGUUGGGGACCGUCUGCUCCUCAGUCCCUGCGCCCCUCUCUGCACUACCUCGGCCCCAUCACCUCCCGGAUCCGCUCUCCACUUCUCCCGCCGCUUCCCUGCCUCUCCUUCCCCCAGCCCGUCUUUCUCCUCCGCCCUUUGCAGCUCUGCCUCCCGCUCCCAGCGUGGUUUUCGCCGUCCCUUCCCUCCUCGUCCCCUUACCGAAUCCAUUCCUGGAAACUUAGGGUCUCAGCUCUGACGCCCCCUUCUUGUAACGAGUCUGGUGGGGGCCGUCAUCCCACACUAGGCUUAGCUUUGGUUUUACUUAGGGCCCUGUUCAUGUCAUGUCUAAAAGUUCGAUUUUCUGUCGGUCUUACUGAGUAACUUCUGCAUUCUCAGAAAGCAGUGUAUGCGCGGACUCCCCGUGGAUGUUACCAACCACAUUUCAUAGAUCUCAGAGCUGAUGGCUGCCUUUCCGUAGCCCCCUAAAGAAUUCGGUUGUGCUUCUGUUUAAGUGUUAACGAUGUGAUUACCGAAUGGGUUUCAUUUCACUAAUGAUGCUGGAAGCUUGAAAUUGACCUUUAGAAAGAAAAACAAUCUGUGGUAUCUAUUGGAUAAAGAGAAAAAUGAGUGCUAAGUGAUUCCCAGUUUAUGUAAACAUCCCAGUUUAUGUAAACACGUAACCAAAACUUUUUUCCUUUUAAUCUUUAAACUUACUUUCUUUACUUCAAAGGUGUGUGCUGUGUAUUUACAUGGAUUCAUUUUAACUAUGGUUCUUAAGCCAAAAGAGCUUGGCAAUGGGCAGAAACCGGGGAGCAACUGGUCUUGAUUUUAAAAUCUUAGUUUUGAGUUAUGCCGACCAUUUUUGAACACCAUUUAUUUAUUUAUUUAUUUUCUAAUAACAUUGAUCUUGCCUUCUGGAUUGUCAUAGGCCACCCUGAGGUUUUCUUAAACUCACCAACCUUCUUGAAUAAAACUUGUGCAUUGCUACGGUUCACUAGACUUGGAAAUACAAUUUGAAUAGAUUCAAAUGUUACAUUUCUGUCAAAAUUUAUCUUGACGAAAAUAACGAUUUUGCAUUUCUUAAUUCUGUGUUAAGGGUCCUUCAAGAAGUUACUAUAUGAAUGCACUUGGGGAAACCAGAGCUACCAGAAUCAUGUUCUUCAGUCAUCAUUGUGAUGAUGCAGAUAUUGUCACUUGCGUGUGCUAAGCUCAGGUCUGAGCACGGUGGAUCCCAUGGGUGUGGCUCUGAGGAAAUUGACGCAGUGGACUGCUGCCGGACAUGGAACUGGAAUCCUCGAAAUCACCCCUCUAAAUGAAGCGAUAUUGAAAGAAAUUAUUGUGUUUGUGGAGAGUUUUAUCUAUAAACAUCCUCAAGAGGCAAAAUUUGUUUUUGUGGAACCACUUGAAUGGAACACAAGUUUGGCGCCCUCAGCAUUUGAAUCAGGUUAUGUUGUCAGUGAAACAACAGUCAAAUCAGAAGAAGUUGAUAAAAAUGGACAGCCUUUGCUAUUUCUCUCUGUACCACAAAUUAAAAUUAGGAGCUUUGGGCAGCUGUCACGCUUGUUACUUAUUGCCAAAACUGGGAAGUUGAAGGAAGCCCAAGCAUGUGUUGAAGCUAACAGAGACCCCAUAGUAAAAAUCCUGGGCUCUGAUUAUAAUACAAUGAAAGAAAACUCAAUUGCAUUAAAUAUUCUUGGCAAAAUUACCAGAGAUGAUGAUCCUGAAAGUGAAAUUAAGAUGAAGAUUGCUAUGCUGCUUAAGCAAUUGGAUCUGCACCUCCUCAAUCAUUCUCUAAAACAUAUUUCAUUAGAAAUAAGUUUAAGUCCCAUGACGGUGAAGAAGGAUAUAGAACUGCUCAAACGUUUCUCAGGAAAAGGAAACCAAACAGUCUUGGAAUCUAUUGAAUAUACCUCAGAUUAUGAAUUUUCAAAUGGAUGUCGAGCCCCACCGUGGAGACAAAUUCGUGGGGAAAUUUGUUAUGUGCUGGUGAAACCUCACGAUGGUGAGACUCUGUGCAUUACUUGCAGUGCAGGAGGAGUAUUUUUAAAUGGUGGCAAAACAGAUGAUGAAGGGGACGUUAAUUAUGAGAGAAAAGGUUCAAUUUAUAAAAACCUUGUCACAUUUUUAAGAGAAAAAUCACCAAAAUUUUCAGAAAAUAUGUCUAAAUUGGGAAUUAGCUUCAGUGAAGACCAGCAAAAGGAAAAGGAUCAGCUUGGCAAAGCCCCCAAGAAGGAAGAAGCAGCUGCCCUCCGCAAAGACAUUUCUGGUUCAGACAAAAGGUCACUGGAGAAGAACCAAAUUAAUUUUUGGAGGAAUCAAAUGACCAAGAGAUGGGAACCAAGCUUAAACUGGAAGACCACUGUUAAUUACAAAGGCAAAGGCUCAGCAAAAGAAAUCCAAGAGGACAAACACACAGGAAAACUUGAAAAACCAAGACCAUCUGUUUCACACGGAAGAGCACAAUUACUUCGGAAGAGUGCUGAAAAGAUUGAGGAAACUGUUAGCGAUAGCUCCUCAGAAAGUGAGGAAGAUGAAGAACCACCUGACCAUCGUCAGGAAGCAAGUGCAGAUUUGCCAUCAGAAUAUUGGCAAAUUCAGAAGCUGGUGAAAUAUUUAAAGGGAGGAAAUCAAACAGCUACAGUGAUUGCGUUGUGUUCAAUGAGGGAUUUCAGCUUAGCUCAAGAAACCUGCCAGUUGGCCAUCAGAGAUGUUGGAGGCCUGGAAGUGCUGAUAAAUUUGCUUGAAACCGAUGAAGUCAAAUGUAAGAUUGGUUCAUUAAAAAUACUGAAGGAAAUCAGUCAUAAUCCUCAAAUCAGACAGAAUAUUGUUGACCUUGGGGGCUUACCAAUUAUGGUGAAUAUACUUGAUUCUCCACACAAGAGUCUAAAAUGUUUGGCAGCCGAGACUAUCGCGAAUGUUGCCAAGUUUAAAAGAGCACGGCGGGUGGUGAGGCAGCACGGGGGUAUCACCAAACUGGUUGCUCUACUAGACUGUGCACAUGAUUCCACAAAACCUGCCCAAUCGAGUCUGUAUGAGGCCAGAGACGUGGAAGUGGCUCGCUGUGGGGCACUGGCCCUGUGGAGCUGCAGUAAGAGUCAUACGAAUAAAGAAGCCAUCCGCAAAGCUGGGGGCAUUCCUCUGUUGGCUCGGCUGCUGAAGACUUCUCAUGAAAACAUGCUAAUUCCAGUGGUGGGGACAUUGCAAGAGUGUGCAUCAGAGGAAAACUACCGGGCUGCAAUCAAAGCAGAAAGGAUCAUUGAAAACCUUGUCAAGAACCUAAAUAGUGAGAAUGAGCAGCUGCAGGAGCACUGCGCCAUGGCCAUUUACCAGUGUGCUGAAGAUAAGGAAACCCGGGACCUCGUUAGGCUGCACGGAGGACUUAAGCCCUUGGCCAGUCUACUCAAUAACACUGACAAUAAAGAGCGGUUAGCUGCUGUCACAGGGGCUAUAUGGAAAUGUUCCAUCAGCAAAGAGAAUGUUACCAAGUUUCGGGAAUACAAAGCCAUUGAAACCUUGGUGGGACUUCUAACAGAUCAGCCUGAAGAAGUACUUGUGAAUGUGGUUGGGGCCUUGGGAGAAUGCUGCCAAGAACGUGAAAACCGAGUCAUUGUCCGGAAAUGUGGUGGCAUUCAACCACUUGUGAACCUCCUUGUUGGAAUAAACCAAGCUCUUCUUGUGAAUGUUACAAAAGCAGUUGGUGCUUGUGCAGUAGAACCUGAAAGUAUGAUGAUAAUUGAUCGCUUAGAUGGAGUUCGUUUGUUGUGGUCCCUGCUGAAAAAUCCUCACCCAGACGUGAAGGCCAGCGCAGCAUGGGCACUCUGUCCAUGCAUCAAAAAUGCAAAGGAUGCUGGGGAAAUGGUUCGUUCCUUUGUUGGUGGUUUGGAACUUAUUGUCAAUUUACUGAAAUCAGAUAACAAAGAAGUUCUGGCAAGUGUAUGUGCUGCCAUUACCAACAUAGCAAAAGAUCAAGAAAAUUUAGCUGUUAUCACAGAUCAUGGAGUUGUUCCUUUAUUGUCCAAACUGGCAAAUACAAAUAACAAUAAAUUGAGACAUCAUCUAGCAGAAGCUAUUUCACGUUGCUGUAUGUGGGGCAGGAAUAGAGUGGCCUUCGGUGAGCACAAAGCAGUGGCUCCACUAGUGCGUUAUCUGAAAUCAAAUGACACCAACGUGCAUCGGGCGACAGCUCAGGCCUUGUACCAACUCUCAGAAGACGCCGAUAACUGCAUCACCAUGCAUGAGAAUGGUGCAGUAAAGCUUCUACUGGAUAUGGUUGGGUCCCCUGACCAGGAUCUCCAGGAAGCUGCAGCUGGUUGUAUAUCCAAUAUCCGCAGGCUGGCUCUUGCUACAGAGAAGGCAAGAUACACUUGAAAUUUAAAUGGACAUUACAAGCUAUCAAAUUCUACAUGACACAGGACAUGUCACUCCCAUGGCCAGAAAGCCUAAAUUGGGAAACAGUUGUUAGCAAACCCUUUCAACCAUCUAAAUGAAAACACACAAAUUGAAAAUGCACAGAAUGUUUUUCAUCUGAAAAUUGCAUGGAGACUUUUGUUUCUAUUUAAUGUUUUCGAGAUAUGACAUGUGAUAAGAUGGAAAGCCAAUAAACCUGUGAUAAGUUUCUAAGAAUAUGAGAAUAUACGUAUAUGAUGUAUUUUUAGUUCAGUGAUGCUUUUGUAUUUGUGGCGAUUUUAAUAAAAAGGAUAUGGCCUUCCCAA